CUCUCUUCCACAGGAGGCCUACACGCCGCCGCUUGUGCUGCAGCCAUGUCUCUAGUGAUCCCUGAAAAGUUCCAGCAUAUUUUGCGAGUACUCAACACCAACAUCGAUGGGCGGCGGAAAAUAGCCUUUGCCAUCACUGCCAUUAAGGUAAGUG